GACAGGUUGCUCAUGGAUCCACCAGUUGUAGUUUAGUGAAGUGGAGAGAUCAAGACCUGGCAGUCCCCCAUAUGUUUUGUGCGUGUGUGUGUGUGUGUGUGUGCGCGUGCCAACUUCACCUUUUACUCUGUCCAUCUUGCCCUUUACCUUAUUCUCCUCCCAUUUCCAUCCCCCCCCACCUUUGUAAAAAUUGCUUCUUCUUGACUAUGGUAGGUGACUUAUCAUUGUUUCUUCCUUUUCUCUCCUUCCUGACUGCCAACAUCCUUAGGACCUCACAUUCCUUCGAAAUUUCAUCUUGUCUUAAGAACCCAAACUGGAAAUAGAAUUCUUCUCUUGACUCCCAUCCCCUAUCUUAUUCUAAAGUCCUUCAGAGUUAGAAUCUCCCCAGACGCACUCAAAAUCUUCACAUCACUGUUCUUCUGCAGGAAGUCCUUCUCUGGCUUCCCUGUCCUAAGCCCCCUACUUAUGGUGAUCUUUUUGGGAAUGUGGGUGCUGGAAGCGGAGGCAGGGGACUUUGGAAAUCCCCAGAACACCAGCCAUGGUGAGCCAAAGAAAUGAACUGUAGAAGCUGGAGAAGCUGAGCUCUUCUGAGGUGUUGGGGUUAUAACUGCCAGAGUCUUUUCCUCCCAAUGGCUGCCUAGAGCUAGGAGAGACUGUGGACUUCCAGAAGUUGGGAUCUGAGGCUUUUCCAAUCGUGCAGGGACUGAAGGCUGCGCUACAUGGUGAAGCAGUUGGAGAAUGGGGAGAUAAACAUUGAGGAGCUGAAGAAAAAUCUGGAGUACACAGCUUCUCUGCUGGAAGCCGUCUACAUAGAUGAGACACGGCAAAUCUUGGACACGGAGGACGAGCUGCAGGAGCUGCGGUCAGAUGCCGUGCCUUCGGAGGUGCGGGACUGGCUGGCCUCCACCUUCACCCAGCAGGCCCGGGCCAAAGGCCGCCGAGCAGAGGAGAAGCCCAAGUUCCGAAGCAUUGUGCACGCUGUGCAGGCUGGGAUCUUCGUGGAACGGAUGUUCCGGAGAACAUACACCUCUGUGGGCCCCACUUACUCUACUGCGGUUCUCAACUGUCUCAAGAACCUGGAUCUCUGGUGCUUUGAUGUCUUUUCCUUGAACCAGGCAGCAGAUGACCAUGCCCUGAGGACCAUUGUUUUUGAGUUGCUGACUCGGCAUAACCUCAUCAGCCGCUUCAAGAUUCCCACUGUGUUUUUGAUGAGUUUCCUGGAUGCCUUGGAGACAGGCUAUGGGAAGUACAAGAAUCCUUACCACAACCAGAUCCACGCAGCCGAUGUUACCCAGACAGUCCAUUGCUUCUUGCUCCGCACAGGGAUGGUGCACUGCCUGUCGGAGAUUGAGCUCCUGGCCAUCAUCUUUGCUGCAGCUAUCCAUGAUUAUGAGCACACGGGCACUACCAACAGCUUCCACAUCCAGACCAAGUCAGAAUGUGCCAUCGUGUACAAUGAUCGUUCAGUGCUGGAGAAUCACCACAUCAGCUCUGUUUUCCGAUUGAUGCAGGAUGAUGAGAUGAACAUUUUCAUCAACCUCACCAAGGAUGAGUUUGUAGAACUCCGAGCCCUGGUCAUUGAGAUGGUGUUGGCCACAGACAUGUCCUGCCAUUUCCAGCAAGUGAAGACCAUGAAGACAGCCUUGCAACAGCUGGAGAGGAUUGACAAGCCCAAGGCCCUGUCUCUACUGCUCCAUGCUGCUGACAUCAGCCACCCAACCAAGCAGUGGUUGGUCCACAGCCGUUGGACCAAGGCCCUCAUGGAGGAAUUCUUCCGUCAGGGUGACAAGGAGGCAGAGUUGGGCCUGCCCUUUUCUCCACUCUGUGACCGCACUUCCACUCUAGUGGCACAGUCUCAGAUAGGGUUCAUCGACUUCAUUGUGGAGCCCACAUUCUCUGUGCUGACUGACGUGGCAGAGAAGAGUGUUCAGCCCCUGGCGGAUGAGGACUCCAAGUCUAAAAACCAGCCCAGCUUUCAGUGGCGCCAGCCCUCUCUGGAUGUGGAAGUGGGAGACCCCAACCCUGAUGUGGUCAGCUUUCGUUCCACCUGGGUCAAGCGCAUUCAGGAGAAUAAGCAGAAAUGGAAGGAACGGGCAGCAAGUGGCAUCACCAACCAGAUGUCCAUUGACGAGCUGUCCCCCUGUGAAGAAGAGGCCCCCCCAUCCCCUGCCGAAGAUGAACACAACCAGAAUGGGAAUCUGGAUUAGCCCUGGGGCUGGCCCAGGUCUUCAUUGAGUCCAAAGUGUUUGAUGUCAUCAGCACCAUCCAUCAGGACUGGCUCCCCCAUCUGCUCCAAGGGAGCGUGGUCGUGGAAGAAACAACCCACCUGAAGGCCAAAUGCCAGAGAUUUGGGGUUGGGGAAAGGGCCCCUCCCCACCUGACACCCACUGGGGUGCACUUUAAUGUUCCGGCAGCAAGACUGGGGAACUUCAGGCUCCCAGUGGUCACUGUGCCCAUCCCUCAGCCUCUGGAUUCUCUUCAUGGCCAGGUGGCUGCCAGGGAGCGGGGAGCUUCCUGGAGGCUUCCCAGGGCCUUGGGGAAGGGUCAGAGAUGCCAGCCCCCUGGGACCUCCCCCAUCCUUUUUGCCUCCAAGUUUCUAAGCAAUACAUUUUGGGGGUUCCCUCAGCCCCCCACCCCAGAUCUUAGCUGGCAGGUCUGGGUGCCCCUUUUCCUCCCCUGGGAAGGGCUGGAAUAGGAUAGAAAGCUGGGGGUUUUCAGAGCCCUAUGUGUGGGGAGGGGAGUGGAUUCCUUCAGGGCAUGGUACCUUUCUAGGACCUGGGAAUGGGGUGGAGAGGACAUCCUCUUCACCCCAGAAUUGCGCUGCUUCAGCCCCAUCUCCAGCCUGAUCCUCUGAAUCUUCCUUCCCUCCCUUUCUGAUACAGUGACUGGGGCAAAAGGAGCCAUUGUGACCAGGGGCUGCGGGAGGCCUUUCCUGGGACCUUCCUUGGGACUGGUCUGGGCCCCUGGGGCUUGUCGCCUGCCCUGAGUCCGGAGCCCUUUGCCUCCUUCCUCUCCCCUGGGGCUGGGAGGCUCCAUCCGACCAAUGUCUGUAAAGUGCUUUGAGGAUCUCCCCAGCAAAGCACCUUCAGAAUGUAUCGACACCAGCUGGGUUAGGGUCAAGGGUGCCUGGGGAGGGUGAGUAAUCCUGCAUUGCUAAAAGAGAGGGUCUGUCCCCUCCUCUCCACGUCCCAGAACUGGCCCAGCUGCAGGCACUAAGAAGCUCCUCCCCUGAGACAAGUGAGGGGUAGUCGGUGAAAGGCAGAUGGACAAGGGGCUCAGGGCUGCUGCCUUCCUGUCCUCUGGAGAGAACCCAGCCAGGCGCGGUGCCCCUUCCUCUCCUCAGGCUCCUCCUUGCCCCCACCUUGCCCCAGGAAAGGCCAAAGUCCAGGUGACUGCCCUCCUUCUUUCUUGUAAAUACCAACCAUGCAUUUGUACAGUGGGCCCUGUUCAUGCGAAAUCCACAUCCAUGGUCUCCUAGACCUGCUACCCUGGUACUUCCACCCUACCCCACCCCGAGAAGGGCAGAGACGCAUGUGACUCACCCCUGCCCUUGGUUUCCCAGACCCCUGCUAUAGCCAGAGAACAAUAAAGAAGGGAGACCAGG